AUCUGUUUUUUUCCCUUCUGAGCAAUGGAGCUUACCAUCUUUAUCCUGAGACUGGCCAUUUACAUCCUGACAUUUCCCUUGUACCUGCUGAACUUUCUGGGCUUGUGGAGCUGGAUAUGCAAAAAAUGGUUCCCCUACUUCUUGGUGAGGUUCACUGUGAUAUACAACGAACAGAUGGCAAGCAAGAAGCGGGAGCUCUUCAGUAACCUGCAGGAGUUUGCGGGCCCCUCCGGGAAACUCUCCCUGCUGGAAGUGGGCUGUGGCACGGGGGCCAACUUCAAGUUCUACCCACCUGGGUGCAGGGUGACCUGUAUUGACCCCAACCCCAACUUUGAGAAGUUUUUGAUCAAGAGCAUUGCAGAGAACCGACACCUGCAGUUUGAGCGCUUUGUGGUAGCUGCCGGGGAGAACAUGCACCAGGUGGCUGAUGGCUCUGUGGAUGUGGUGGUCUGCACCCUGGUGCUGUGCUCUGUGAAGAACCAGGAGCGGAUUCUCCGCGAGGUGUGCAGAGUGCUGAGACCGGGAGGGGCUUUCUAUUUCAUGGAGCAUGUGGCAGCUGAGUGUUCGACUUGGAAUUACUUCUGGCAACAAGUCCUGGAUCCUGCCUGGCACCUUCUGUUUGAUGGGUGCAACCUGACCAGAGAGAGCUGGAAGGCCCUGGAGCGGGCCAGCUUCUCUAAGCUGAAGCUGCAGCACAUCCAGGCCCCACUGUCCUGGGAGUUGGUGCGCCCUCAUAUCUAUGGAUAUGCUGUGAAAUAGUGUGAGCUGGCAGUUAAGAGCUGAAUGGCUCAAAGAAUUUAAAGCUUCAGUUUUACAUUUAAAAUGCUAAGUGGGAGAAGAGAAACCUUUUUUUUGGGGGGCGGUUUUUUUGGUUUGUUGUUGGUUUUUUUUUUUUUUUUGGCGGGAAGAAAGAGUUUUGCUCUUGUUGCCCAGGCUGGAGUGCAAUGACGUGAUCUCCGCUCACUGCAACCUCCACCUCGCGGGUUUAAGCGAUUCUUCUGCCUCAGCCUCCCUAGUAGCUGGGAUUACAGGUGCCCACCACCAUGCCCAGCUAAUUUGUAUUUUUAGUUGAGACAGGGUUUCACUACGUUGGCCAGGCUGGUCUUGAACUCCUGAUCUCAGGCAAUCCACCCACCUCAGCCUCCCAAAGUGCUGGGAUGACAGGCGUGAGCAACCGCACCCAGCUUAAGGUUUUUUUGUUUUGUUUUGAGACGGAGUUUUCGCUCUUGUUGCCCAGGCUGGAGUGCAAUGCUGUGAUCUCAGCUUACCACAACCUCCACCUCCCGGGUUCAAGUGAUUCACCUGCCUCAGCCUCCUGAGUAGCUGGUAUUACAGGCAUGCGUCACCACGCCGGCUAAUUUUGUACUUUUAGUAGAGAUGGUGUUUCCCCACGUUGGUCAGUCUGGUCUCAAAUUCCUGACCUCAGGUGAUCUGCCUGCCUCGGCCUCCCAAAGUGCUGUGAUUACAGACGUCAGCCACCAUGCCUGGCCUGAAACCUUUUUUAGGUAAAGUUGAAUUCCAUCCUUAAAAGUUUCUGUUAUAUCCUAUUUAGCCAUUUUCUAUUGUCUCCCAAAGAAUUCACAUCAAAAAAACAGCUUUGAACUCCCCCUUCAAAGGAAACAGUCGACUUUCAUAAUUAGCAUCUACCAUUAUCCCCAAAUCUUAUUUUAUUCAUUGACUUGAAAUUUUUUCCAAUUGCUUUUUUUUUUUUUUUUUUAAGGUUAAGAGCAGAGGUUUACUAGGCCAAAGAAAGAGAAUAGCUCUCUGUUGCAGAGAGGGGUCCUGGAGAAAUGGGUUACCCCAGUUGUCUUAUUUAAAUGGUUACCCAUCAGAUUUUAAUUUUAUCUUCUCUUUGAGAGCUUGGUAAUAAGAAGCACUUAAAUCACUCCAAAGAAGACUUUAAAAAGGGAGCAGUGAAAAGGUCUUAAUAAUUUAUUGAUUGAAUUAAGAAAUACUAGCUAAUUAAGAAUCUGAGUCUAAACAGCACAGAUUUUUUCUUUCUGCUUUUAAAUUGUGUUUUAAAAAAAGAGACAGGGGGCUGGGCGUGGUGGCUCACGCCUGUAAUCCUAGCACUUUGGGAGGCCGAGGCGGGUGGAUCACGAGGUAGGAGUUAAAGACCAGCCUGGCCAACAUGGCAAAACCCUACUAAAGAUACAAAAAAAAAAAAAAAUUAGCCAGGCGUGGUGGUGGGUGCCUGUAAUCCCAGGUACUUGGAAGGCUGAGGCAGGAGAAUCUCUUGAACCCAGAAGGCGAAGGUUGCAGUGAACCGAGAUCAUGCCAUUGUACUCUAGCCUGGGUGACAAGAGCAAGACUCCGUCUCAAAAAAAAAAAAAAAAAAAAAAAGAAGUAGAGACAGGGAGACAGGGUCUCACUGUGUUGCCUAGGCCGGUCUUGAACUCCUGGGCUCAAGUGAUUCUCCCACCUUGACCUCCUAAAUUGUUGGGAUUACAGGUGUGAGACAGUGCACCUGGCCGAAAUAGCUCAAGUUUCUGAAAAACAAAUCUGAAUCUAUUUGUUAUUCUUAGCGUCACUGGUCUGGCUUUCAGAAUUAACAUACAAGGUUGCCACACCUAGUUCUGCCCAGCUUUAUGUCUUUUAUUCCAGUAUUCCACCAAAGUUUGUUUUCCUGCAUUCCAGUUCUCAAGUCUUAAGAUAAAGAUUGUACUUGACAGUUUAGUAUAUCCAUAAAACUAUUUGAGGUGGUUAAGGUUCUUGGGUUCAUUUUCCUUAAUACUUUGCUGAAUAUUGUAGAUUGUAGGCAAUGAAAAAGUCUACUAAAUUAGGAAAACCUUGAAUAAUUAGGUAUCCUAGGUAAGAGCCCCUAAACAUCAAGCAAUCUGUGAGUCUGUAAAGAAAUAAAUAUUUUUUGGAUUAUUCUUAUCUAAUUCCACCCCUGUUGGAAGAUGAUUUCUUUGUUCUUUGCAACUAUGGAAGCUGUGAAAAUCAUCACAAGUGCCUCUGAAAGCGAGUGUUAGGUUGGUUAGAGGGUUUAAUAUUUUCUGCAAUGGUUUGUAGGAAUUUUAAUAAAUGUAGUAUAUUUUCUGAGAUGAUUUUGUAAAAGUACUAUUUUAAAUAUCAAAUCAACCAAUAAAUUCACAUUUGUGUUAGGAACAGAAA